GUGGCCGCAGCGCUCAGCUCCUGCGCCCCGACCCCGCCAUGGCCCCCCGGCCCCUCCUGCUGCUGCUGCUGCUCCUCGGGGGCUCCGCCGCGCGCCCCGCGCCCCCCAGGGCCCGGCGACACUCAGACGGGACGUUCACCAGCGAGCUCAGCCGCCUGCGGGAGGGCGCGCGGCUCCAGCGGCUGCUACAGGGCCUGGUGGGGAAGCGCAGCGAGCAGGACGCAGAGAACAGCAUGGCCUGGACCAGGCUCAGCGCGGGUCUGCUCUGCCCGUCAGGGUCCAACAUGCCCAUCCUGCAGGCCUGGAUGCCCCUGGACGGGACCUGGUCUCCCUGGCUGCCCCCUGGGCCUAUGGUUUCAGAACCAGCUGGCGCUGCUGCAGAAGGAACCUUGCGGCCCAGAUGAGGAAGGAACCCCCUCACCACCUGCCCGGCCCAGGAGCGCAGCUGCAUUUGGGGUGGGGGGCAGGAUGGGGGAGAGGGGGAGGGGUGGUACUUGGCACCAAUAAAGGAGGAAUCAGACCCAGA